CUCUCCACUGCCUGCCCGCCACCGUGCAAGCUCUGGCCGGCGCUGCCCACAGUCCCCAUGGUGGGCAGCCCCCGCGGCGGGGACCCCUGAUCGGCAGCGGCAUGCCAGGGAAGCCCAAGCACCUGGGCGUCCCCAACGGGCGCAUGGUUCUGGCUGUGUCAGAUGGAGAGCUGAGCAGCACGACGGGGCCCCAGGGCCAGGGCGAGGGCCGCGGCAGCUCUCUCAGCAUCCACAGCCUCCCCAGUGGUCCCAGCAGCCCCUUCCCAACCGAGGAGCAGCCUGUGGCCAGCUGGGCCCUGUCCUUCGAGCGGCUGUUGCAGGACCCGCUGGGCCUGGCUUACUUCACUGAGUUCCUGAAGAAGGAGUUCAGCGCGGAAAACGUGACUUUCUGGAAGGCCUGCGAGCGCUUCCAGCAGAUCCCGGCCAGCGAUACCCAGCAGCUAGCUCAGGAGGCCCGCAACAUCUACCAGGAGUUCCUGUCCAGCCAGGCGCUGAGCCCAGUGAACAUCGACCGUCAGGCCUGGCUUGGCGAGGAGGUGCUGGCCGAGCCCCGGCCGGACAUGUUUCGGGCACAGCAGCUUCAGAUCUUCAACUUGAUGAAGUUCGACAGCUAUGCGCGCUUCGUCAAGUCCCCGCUGUACCGCGAGUGCCUGCUAGCCGAAGCCGAGGGACGCCCUCUGCGGGAACCUGGCUCCUCGCGCCUCGGCAGCCCUGACGCCACGAGGAAGGUGCGUGGGACUGGGCGAGGGACUGGGCGAGGCAGGGGGUCCUGCGGACCGCGUGCAAGAGGGGACGCCUCCGGGUGCAGAUCUGCGAGUCUGUGCCCACGGUCUGCAUGCGGGCUGGGGCCCAGCCCGGUGCCAGCGCCUCCCCUGUACCCACAGAAGCCGAAGCUGAAGCCCGGGAAGUCGCUGCCGCUGGGUGUGGAGGAGUUGGGGCAGCUGCCACCCGUUGAGGGUCCUGGGGGCCGCCCUCUCCGCAAGUCCUUCCGCCGGGAGCUGGGCGGGACUGCAAACGCCGCCUUGCGCCGAGAGUCUCAGGGCUCCCUCAACUCCUCCGCCAGCCUGGACCUUGGCUUCCUAGCCUUCGUCAGCAGCAAAUCUGAGAGCCACCGGAAGAGCCUUGGGAGCACGGAGGGUGAAAGUGAAAGCCGGCCAGGGAAGUACUGCUGUGUGUACCUGCCCGAUGGCACAGCCUCCUUGGCCCUGGCCAGACCUGGCCUCACCAUCCGAGACAUGCUGGCAGGGAUCUGUGAGAAACGAGGCCUCUCUCUACCUGACAUCAAGGUCUACCUGGUGGGCAAUGAACAGAAGGCCCUGGUCCUGGAUCAGGACUGCACCGUGCUGGCGGAUCAGGAAGUGCGGCUGGAAAACAGGAUCACCUUCGAGCUGGAGCUGACGGCGCUGGAGCGCGUGGUACGAAUCUCAGCCAAGCCCACCAAGCGGCUGCAGGAGGCGCUGCAGCCCAUUCUGGAGAAGCACGGCUUGAGCCCGCUAGAGGUGGUGCUGCACCGGCCAGGCGAGAAACAGCCUCUGGAUCUGGGGAAGCUAGUGAGCUCGGUGGCGGCCCAGAGACUGGUUUUGGACACUCUUCCAGGUGUGAAGAUCUCCAAAGCCCGUGACAAAUCUCCCUGCCGCAGCCAGGGCUGCCCACCUAGAACUCAGGAUAAGGCCACCCAUCCCCCUCCAGCGUCCCCCAGUUCUCUGGUGAAGGUGCCCAGUAGUGCCACUGGAAAGCGGCAGACCUGUGACAUCGAAGGCCUGGUGGAGCUGCUGAACCGGGUGCAGAGCAGCGGGGCCCACGACCAGAGGGGCCUUCUGAGGAAAGAGGACCUGGUACUUCCAGAAUUUCUGCAGCUGCCCGCCCAAGGGCCCAGCUCCGAGGAGACCCCACCACAGACCAAAUCAGCAGCCCAGCCCAUCGGGGGAUCCUUGAACUCCACCACCGACUCAGCCCUCUGACAGCUACCCAACAGUCCAGGACAGCUGCAUGGCACCCGGCGGGCCGAGCAUGCCAUGGGUCCGCUCUGCAUGCCCUGUCUGUGCCAUGAGUGUCCCUGGCCCCUUCCUGCCAUGGGCAGGCCCGCAGGAAGAGCCGGUAGGGGUGGAAAGGGGACUCAGAUGAGACACACCCCACAGCUGCCACCGCCUUGUCCCUCAACAAGCUCACCCCCAAUCCCUUGCAGCCAGGCCACAAUGGGGGAGGUGAGUCCAGCCCCUUGGAACAGGCUUGCCCAACAUGGAGGGAUGGCGUUGGCAGUGCCAGCCUCCCCAGCCUGUGCCAAGCUUCAACAGGGGCAAGAGGAGGGGCCGGCCCCUCCUCAGGAAGCUGGUAUGAGUAAGGCCUUGAGGGUGCAGGCAGGCAGCCCUGUACCCCACCCACAUAGACUAUACUGUACAUACAGAUUUUGCAGUAGGCUUGGGGCAGCUGGGUUUGUCCUUGAUGUAUGAUACUGUUAUUAUAAUAAUUAUUAUUAUUCUGC